ACUGGACUCUGAAACGGGCAUGUACAGAGAAGAGGAGACCCCAACACGCUUCAAGCUUUGAGUGGAGAGGACACAGCCUCUGCUGGGACAGGGAACAGAGGGAUGCGGAGACCCUGAAGAUGCUUUUGGACAGUGGUCUGAGGUUGGGACAGUGGCAGGAGAUACCAUUCACCCAGGAUCUCCAGGACAAGAGAUCAGCCUGGCAGUUACAUGUGUUUUUUUUCAAACUGGUUGCCAGGUUGGCAUGAGCGAUGACAUCAGAGAUUCCGACCUUCCUGAUUGGAGGGACCGGACUCUGUCGGCACCUGGGAGUUCAGUUGGACAACAGUAACUUCUCAGAGCUGUUCUCCACUCCUGACUUCUCCCAGCCUCGAGAAUUGAUAACACACUCUUCUGGAUCCCAGCAGUGUCCAGAAGAAGACCAAGGACAGAACAGAGACUAGGUUUGGUGAGAUGGGACAGAUUUUGGGAAAGAUCAUGAUGAGCCAUCAACCGCAGCCCCAGGAAGAGCAGAGCCCCCAGCGGAGCACCUCAGGGUACCCCCUCCAGGAGGUGGUGGAUGAUGAAGUGUCGGGACCAUCAGCCCCUGGGGUAGAUCCCAGCCCCCCACGUAGGUCCCUUGGCUGGAAAAGGAAGAGGGAAUGUUUGGAUGAAUCUGAUGAUGAGCCAGAGAAGGAGCUCGCCCCUGAGCCUGAGGAGACCUGGGUGGCGGAGACGCUGUGUGGCCUCAAGAUGAAGGCGAAGCGACGGCGAGUGUCGCUCGUGCUCCCUGAGUACUACGAGGCCUUCAACAGGCUGCUUGAGGAUCCUGUCAUUAAAAGACUCCUGGCCUGGGACAAAGAUCUGAGGGUGUCGGACAAGUAUCUCCUGGCUAUGGUCAUAGCGUAUUUCAGCCGGGCCGGCCUCCCCUCCUGGCAAUACCAACGCAUUCAUUUCUUCCUGGCUCUCUAUCUGGCCAAUGACAUGGAGGAGGACGAUGAGGCCCCCAAACAAAACAUCUUCUACUUCCUGUACGAGGAGACCCGCUCUCAUAUACCCUUGCUCCGUGAGCUUUGGUUCCAGUUAUGCCGUUACAUGAACCCGAGGGCCAGGAAGAACUGCUCUCAGAUAGCCUUGUUCCGGAAGUAUCGGUUCCACUUCUUUUGUUCCAUGCGCUGCAGGGCUUGGGUUUCCCUGGAGGAGUUGGAAGAGAUCCAGGCUUAUGACCCAGAGCACUGGGUGUGGGCGCGAGAUCGCGCCCACCUUUCCUAGAGCUCCAGGGACCGUGGAGGCCUGAGGUCAUCGGCCUGAGAGAAGGUACAUCUGCAUCCUCCGGGGUAAAGGCAGAAUAUUGGGGUCUAUUUCGGAAAUCCAAGGAACCCAAUUGCUUGAUCUGGCUUCAAGCCUGGGCAACGUGGCGAGAUCCCCUCUCCACAAAAAUACAAAAAUUAGCCAGGCGAUGUGGGAGGCAUCUCUACUCCCAACUACUCAGGAGGCUGAGGCGGGAGGAUCGCUGGAGCCUGGGAGGUCGGGGCUGCAGGGAGCCCUGAUCCUGCCACUGCACUCCAGCCCAGGCGACAGAGUGAGACCCUGCCUCAAAAAUAAUCAUAAAUACUGAGUUCGGGGAGGUUCAUUAUGAUUGAUGCACUUGAGUUACCGAUCUGGGUCGAGGGUUCAGUGAAGCUUUGGUUUACAUCUUGUGCAGCUAACCAUGUUGAGCACAGAGCAUGAGACUUUGUCAUGAGGAGGGAGGAUUAUGGAUUAGGCUUCUGGACUCGUGGUUCGUGAUGUUGUCACAUUAGAAACAGAUCUAGCACGGUUACAAGUUUAGAUCUGAAGUGACACAAAAGGCCCCAGCUGUGAUGAAGUCCAAAGCCACAUUCUCUGAGGGUGCCCUACUCCCUGGGAAGACCCACCCAAAGUCCUUGCUAUGAAGCAGAUCACUGGGGCUGACCUUGGGUGUAUUAAGUUUUGGAGUCAGGGUCACCAAAGUGUGAGUUUCACAGUUGAACACGAUGGUUCAGAAGCAGGGUAUAGAAUGAAAGGCAGGAGAUAAAAUUGCACUUCUCAAUUGCUCUGAACUCUAGCUAGACUUGACAUGGGACGUGAAUAACCUUCCUGUCUAGAGAGCUGCCUCCUUGAAGUGUGACAUUGUCUCUCUCACUUCCAGAACACCGGACCCAGGGGAGAUGUGGAUUUUCAGCAGGAACUUUAUUCCAAUGCUAAUGGCAGACAUCAGGAAGGAGGAGAGGAACCAUUUGUGCAGAUCAUCUAGAAGAACCUGGACCAUUCUUGACAGAGCUGAAUACAGUGAUCACGUUGUCCUCCAAGGAGCAGGGGUGGGGUGGGGUACUUCUAGGAGUCCUUGGAGAAAAGUAAGAAACCAGGAGUGUUUCCAGUUCCACCCUUUCCUGCGGCACCACCUCCCUUUUUAUAUUGCUGAAUGCCAACCUCCCUGGGGCGGAACCUGGAGGUCCUAUUUCUUAUGGACUUGGUUGCCACAGUCCAGGAGCAUUUGAAGGCACAGUGCAGGGGCUCAGAUUGGCACAGAAUUCUUUGUGAAAUAUGAGUGCCACAGACUGUAACAGAUAGCUUCAUGCACACUAUGCAUUUUAUUGGUUUGUUUGGAAAAUGUUGGCCAUUGAAUUAUUAAUAGGUUUAUUUCAAAUAGUUUGGAAAUUGUUGUACUUUUGAAAACAUGCUGUUCCUGUAGAGUUUUUUGAUGAGAGUUAUAGUUGUUAUAUAUACCUAAAGAUAAUUUUCUUUUCAUUUUUAAGUGAGAAUUCUUUUUAUCCUAAAUCUUUUAUUAUCUUUAAAUUUUUUUCUGUAUUAUUAUAUGUGCUCCUGAAGCGAGCACUCUUUUUAUCUAUGAUACUUCCAUAAUAAUCUCUUCUAUUUAUAGCUAUUGGUAGUUCCCCACCAGAAAAAAACAUAAUUCUGGUGAUAGAAAUUUUUAUUUGCUGUUUAGGUUUGUGACUGAAUUGUGAGAAUUCAGUUGUGAUUUUUAACAUGUCUCAGAUAUAUAUACUAACACGUCUAAUAUAUACUAUCUAUUUUAUUGGUUUAUUUUGAAAAACAUGGGUAUAGAAUUAUUUAAAUAUUAUUUUAUUUAUUGAAAUAUUUAUUAAAUAUGUUUAUUUAUUUAAAUAUUAUUAUUACUUUAAAUAUUAUUUUAAAUAUUUUGGAAAUACUGGUAUUUUUGAAUAGAUGCUGUUUCUACAAAGCUGUGUGAUGGGUGUUAUAACUGUUGUAUACACAUACAUAUAAUUUUGUUUUCCUUUUUAAGAGAGGAUUCUUUUCAUCCUAAAUCUUUUACCUUUCAAUCUUUGUAUCUAUUAUUACACGUGCUGCUGAAGGGGAGCAUGGUUUUUAUCUAUGAUACUUAGUUAACAUAUAUAUUACAUUUAUAGCUAUGUGGUAGUUCCCCUAAAUUCUUGUAAAAAUAAAUUUUUAUUUGAUAUUUAGUGUAUGUUUGAAAUGUGAGAAUUCAGAUGGAAUUUUUUAUCUUGUUUUGGCAUGUUUGUAUGUUACUUUAAAGAGGAUGUGUGUUCUAAAGGAGGACAUGAGCUGUGUGUUUUCAAGAGAACAGUGCAGUGCAUCUCUUGGGGAAACAUAAUAAAGAUGAACUUUUCUCACCUUCA